AGAGGGGACAUUUCACCAUGGAAUAUGAAGUCAAGAAAGGGAAGAAGUUCCUAGGUGGUGCUGCUGGUCCAGGAAUCUCAUGUUGAGAAAUGCUGUUCUAGAUGGAACUCAAACUUUCUUUUGAGAUUCAGAUGGCUGGUCUGGGCUGAGCCCCAGAAUUUACACCUUUAACCUUGAUCCAGGCCAUUUUUAUGCAGGGCUUUGUAUCCCCCAUCCGAAGGCUGGUGUUCCCCAAGGCCGGGCGCCGGGCAGCCUGUAGGAGCAGCGUGAGCCGCCGGCCCCUGCACUCGAUGCCCCUUUAUCCCCCCGACUACCUCAUCGACCCCCAGAUUCUGCUGUGUGACUACCUGGAGAAAGAGGUCAAGUUCCUGGGCCACCUUACCUGGGUGACUUCCUCACUGAACCCCUCCAGUCGGGACGAGCUCCUGCAGCUGCUAGACACCGCCAGGCAGCUGAAGGAGCUGCCGCUGAAGACCACGGCGGAGCAGGACAGCAUCCUGAGCCUGUCUGCCCGCUGCCUGCUGCUCACCUGGCGCGACAAUGAAGAGCUCAUUCUGCGAAUCCCUACGCACGAGAUCGCCGCCGCCUCCUACCUGCAGGACGACGCGCUGCACCUGCUAGUGCUCAAGACCGGUCUGGGUGUGGACCCGGUGCCGGCCGGCGUGGAUGCCAGCCCAGGCGGCGCAGGACGCGACCCCGGCCCGCCAGGCGGGGCGCCCGAGAAGCGGCGGGUGGGCACCGCGGAGCGGCGCCACACCAUCUGCAGCCUGGACUGGCGGAUGGGGUGGGGUGGGGGCGCCGCGGAGGCCCGGGCCGGGGGAGGCGGCGGCGGCAGCUUGGAGCGCCAGCGCGCCGGGGCGCGGGCGUCGGGCAGCUGGGAGCGACGGCAGACGUUCAGCGGCAGCUGGGAGCGGCGGCACGGAGGCGGCGGCGGCGGCGGCGGCGCGGGAAAGCCGGGCGGUAGCUGGGAGCGGAGGCAGGCGGGCAGCGGCGGGGGAGGCAGCUGGGAGCGGCGCCACCCCGGCCCCAACCCGCUCGACCCGCAGGACCCCAGCCCCGACGCCUACUGCAACCUGGUCAUCCUGGCUGUAGCCAACAGGGACGCUGCAGAGGAGUCCUGCGCACUCAUCUGUCAGGUCUUCCAGAUCAUCUACGGGGACCAGAGUAUUGAGUGUGUGGACCGGGCUGGCUACCACUACACAUCCACACCUGAACGGCCAUGGCUCUGCAGCCGCAGUGAGAGCUGCCACACAGAUGGGACGUAUGCCUAUGAUGCCGACUUCAGCUGCUGCAGCUCCUUUAAUGGCUCCCAGGACACCUUUGAAGCAUGUUACAGCGGCACGUCCACACCUUCUUUCCAUGGCUCCCACUGCAGCGGCAGCGACCACAGCAGUCUGGGCUUGGAGCAGUUACAGGAUUACAUGGUCACGUUGCGGAGUAAGCUGGGGCCCCUCGAGAUCCAGCAGUUUGCGAUGCUGCUGCGGGAGUACCGGCUGGGGCUGCCCAUCCAGGACUAUUGCACAGGCCUGCUGAAGCUCUACGGAGACCGGCGCAAGUUCCUCCUCCUUGAUCUGCAGAGAGGACGCUUCCCCUGUGGAAGGGAAAGGGAACGUGUCCUGGGGACUCACCAUGCCCCUCGGCUCGCAGGGAUGCGGCCCUUCAUCCCGGACCAGGACAUCGGCUACUUCGAGGGCUUCCUGGAGGGCGUGGGCAUCCGCGAGGGCGGCAUCCUCACUGACAGCUUCGGCCGCAUCAAGCGCAGCAUGAGCUCCACGUCGGCCUCCGCAGUGCGCAGCUACGAUGGCGCGGCGCAGCGGCCCGAGGCACAGGCCUUCCACCGGCUGCUGGCUGACAUCACGCACGACAUCGAGGCGCUGGCCCCCGAUGACGACGACGACGACGAGGAUGAGCCCCGGGGCUCCAGGGGCGGGAGCGACGCCGCAGAAGACAACUACCUGUAGCCACCGCCCCUGCGGACGGCGUGGCUCAGCAGCCCACCUCUGAGUCUCAGCUUUGCUUCGGGGACCCUAUCCCCAGGGCCCCCCCAUCACACCUGGCGGGGCCGGGGGGUCUUCACUCCAGGGUCUCGCUCCCUGCCCUUGGGGCCCGGGGCCAUGCAGUACCUGGAGUGUCCUGCAGGGGGAAAGCGAAGCCGGGCCCUGAAGUCCGGGGCAGUCACCCGGGGCUCCUGGGCCGCUCUGCCGGGCUGGGGCUGAGCAGCGAUCCUGCUUUGUCCCAGAAGUCCAGAGGGAUCAGCCCCAGAACACACCCUCCUCCCCGGGACGCCGCAGCUUUCUGGAGGCUGAGGAAGGCAUGAAGAGUGGGCUCCACCUGCUGGCCGACUGAGAAAAGAAUUUCCAGAACUCGGUCCUAUUUUACAGAUUGAGAAACUAUGGUUCAAGAAGAGAGGACGGGGCUUGAGGGAAUCUCCUGAUUCUCCUUAUAUGACCUCAAACUGACCAUACUAAACAGUGUAGAAGGUCUUUUUAAGGCUCUAAAUGUCAGGGUCUCCCAUCCCCUGAUGCCUGACUUGUACAGUCAGUGUGGAGUAGACGGUUUCCUCCACCCAGGGUUGACUCAGGGGGAUGAUCUGGGUCCCAUUCUGGUCUUAAGACCCCAAACAAGGGUUUUUUCAGCUCCAGGAUCUGGAGCCUCUAUCUGGUUAGUGUCGUAACCUCUGUGUGCCUCCCGUUACCCCAUCUGUCCAGUGAGCUCAGCCCCCAUCCACCUAACAGGGUGGCCACAGGGAUUACUGAGGGUUAAGACCUUAGAACUGGGUCUAGCACCCGAUAAGAGCUCAAUAAAUGUUGUUCCUUUCCACAUCAAA